AUGGAGUCCCUGCGUCCCGGCUCCACGGUGCGGGAGUCCUCCGUGGUGGCUGAAUUCGCCUUUCAGGCCCUAUUGAAUUCGCUGUUGAUAAUCUGCUUCUCCCUGAGCUGCUGUCGCCCACACUCGCCGCUGGCCGUGCUUGUUUUUCUCCUGGAACUGGGGCCGGUGUCCCUGUUGACCUUGUCCCGGGUAGCUGAGCCCAGGGGACUCUCCUUCCUAGGGUUACCGCUCAGUAUCAGCACAGCCACAACGUCCAGCCAGGGAGGGCAUCCGAGGCCCUCAGCACCCACCCCGGGGGUCCGGCCCGCGUCAGGCUGCGAGUUCCCGAGUCCCUGGACCCAGCUGUGCCUGCUGGGGUCAGCGCAGUCUGUGAGCCUCGACCCCCAGCUCCCAGCAAGGCCUCCCAGCAAGGCCUGUCGGAACCCAGCGGAGACCGGCGGCUGGGGCUUGUCCUCGAGCGGGGGCGCAGGACACGGGGCGCGGGGCUCCUGCCCUUGCAGCGUCCUGUCAGGAUGGACGACCCAAGCCAGACGGCGCUCCCUCCCGCCACACCUGGCCGUACUGGCCUCCAGCCAUGCCGGUGCUGCCGAGGCCCCCGUGUGGGACAGGCCCCCGCUCCCGCCCGUCCUCCUGGCUGCAUCUGCACCCGCCCGUACCCGCACCGGGCCUCACUGGCCCCUUCUCAGACCGGCACAGCCAGAAACGGGAAUCCAAGUCCAGGGUUUACCUCUGGGGCCCUGGGGACCACGUGGCUGCCUAGGAAACGCAGCCCAACAGCAGGCUAGCUCCGAGGCAGAAGCCUUUUCUCCAGGAAGGGCCGGCGAGGAGCCCGACAGCCAGCUCCACGGAGAAGGCCUCAGAGCGGGCAGGCCAGGAAUGCCCUCCCGCCCACCCUGGGAGACCGGCCCCUCCUCAGACCGUUUCUGGGAGGUCGAACACCUGUCCACUUUGAUUUUCCCUGACUUCGCAACAUCUGUUUACGAACGGUUUUGCCCAGCUCAUGACUUUUUUGGGGAGUUUUUGUACUAGAACUGUUGAACUUUGCUUAGGGACAUUACACAAGACGCAAACUGCAGGAGACGUUUGGGAGACACACGGCAGGCCUUGUCCGGAAUCUUUUCUGUUUACCGAAAGUUCAUUUGAUUUUCAUGGCCAGUUAACUUGAGGCCUAGGGACAGUGCCGGAUUGCAGCAGGGCAAGGACUAAACAUCUGGACCCUAGGAGAGGAGGAGCCCCCCGAAGCCCCGCCUGCCACGCCACCACCACUCAGCACCUGAGGAGCUCCAGAAGCUUCCAGAA